GCCCGGCAACAACAAGUCCCGUCGGGUGGCAGCGGCUGGCGGCAAAACCUCUCGAGUGAGCCCCUGCCCGAGUGCCGCGGGGGAGAGGCCGCGAGCGGGACCGAGAAGUGGGCUGGGAGCAGAGGUCGCGGAGGUGGCGAGCGAGGCCGGGGCCCAGGCGGGGACCGGCAGGGGCCCGGGAGUGGCGGGCACGCCAGGGUCAGGGUGCCGGGCGAGGGAGGGGGCCCGGGGUUGGGGAAGGGGGCCCGGGGAGGGAGGUAAACAGCCCUGCAGGCCUCGGGGCACCGUUGCUGGGCGGCGCCGGCGGCAUGUGCGAGGGCCCGUCCCGCAUCUCGGGGCCCAUCCCCCCAGACCCGACGCUCUGUCCUGACAACUACAGGCGGCCGACCUCGGCUCAAGGGCGCCUCGAGGGAAACGCGCUGAAGCUGGACUUGCUGACUUCCGACCGGGCCCUGGACACCACCGCUCCCCGUGGCCCCUGCAUCGGUCCCGGUGCCGGAGAGAUCCUGGAGCGCGGCCAGCGCGGCGUCGGGGACGUGCUGUUGCAACUCGAGGGGAUCUCCCUAGGUCCUGGGGCCUCUCUCAAGAGGAAGGACCCUAAGGACCAUGAGAAGGAGAACCUGAGGCGGAUCAGGGAGAUUCAGAAGCGCUUCAGAGAACAGGAGCGCAGCCGGGAGCAGGGCCAGCCCAGGCCCCUGAAAGCUCUGUGGCGCUCACCCAAGUACGACAAGGUGGAGUCCCGGGUCAAGGCCCAGCUCCAGGAGCCUGGCCCUGCCUCUGGGACAGAGUCUGCCCACUUCCUGCGGGCGCACUCCCGCUGCGGCCCUGGCCUCCCACCACCCCAUGUAUCUAGUCCCCAGCCAACCCCACCAGGUCCCGAAGCUAAGGAGCCAGGCCUGGGGGUGGACUUCAUUCGUCACAAUGCACGAGCUGCCAAGAGAGCCCCCCGGAGGCAUUCCUGCUCACUGCAGGUCCUGGCACAAGUGCUAGAGCAGCAGCGGCAGGCCCAGGAGCACUACAAUGCCACGCAGAAGGGCCAUGUGCCACAUUACUUGUUGGAGCGCAGGGACCUGUGGCGGCGGGAGGCCGAGGCCCGCAAGCAGAGCCAGCCGGACCCUGCCAUGCCCCCAGGCCACACGCGCAUGCCUGAGAACCAGCGGCUGGAAACACUGACCAAGCUGCUCCAGAGCCAGAGCCAGCUGCUGCGUGAGCUGGUACUGCUGCCUGCUGGGGCAGACUCACUGAGAGCCCAGAGCCACCGUGCUGAGCUGGACCGGAAGCUGGUGCAGGUAGAGGAGGCCAUCAAGAUCUUUUCUCGGCCCAAAGUCUUCGUGAAGAUGGACGACUGAGCCCCUUUGGGGGACAGUGGCAAGGAGCUCCAUGCUGAGGAUCGCCACAUGGCUGCAAAGGACAGGGUUGGACCCAAUCCCAGAGCAGAGGUCUGAAGACAGGAGCAGGGGGGUGGCCAGUGUCCCUAGAGCACUCUUCCCAGUCACCAGUGGCUGCAGAAGGGCCACCCUAGCCUUUUAACUGCUUUGUCAAAAUUAAACAUUUUGUACACAGGA